AGGGCCUCUUUCGCCGCCGCCGCCGCCGCCAGCCAGCCAGCUUCUUCCCAGGACCAUAGGCCACUCCAGCCUCAGCUUCUCCUGGCCCCCUCCCUGUGUCUGUUCCUGUCCCCGAGCCUCUGGCCUCUGAUGCCUUCAGGAGCUUGGGCCUCUCCUGCUCCACUCCUAAACUUCAGCUUCUCAGCAAACAGGCCUCCCAAGUCCCUGCUUCUCCCUCUCAGGCCUUGCUAACCUCACCAGCUCUAGGGCCUGGCCAGGCCUCCCAGGCUCCCUCCUCCACCCCAACCCCUUCUCACUCAUGGAGCCCUUGGGACUGGUCGUGCAUGGGAAAGCUGAACCUUUUUCCGCAGCACUCCGAAGCCUUGUCAACAACCCGCGAUACAGUGAUGUUUGCUUCGUGGUUGGUCAAGAACGGCAGGAGGUAUUUGCCCAUCGGUGCUUGUUGGCCUGUAGAUGCAACUUCUUCCAGCGACUUCUGGGCACAGAGCCAGGCCCCGGGGUGCCCAGUCCUGUGGUGCUAAGCACUGUGCCAACUGAGGCCUUCCUGGCAGUGCUGGAGUUCCUAUAUACCAACAGUGUCAAGCUGUACCGCCACUCUGUGAGCCUGCUGACCAGGGGCCUGGGUGGGAGAGGUGGGGGGUGCCAGAGGCAGGAGUUUGCCCAUUACACUGUGGGCACAGGGCAGGGGAAACUCCCUUCCACUCCCCCAACCACCCACUCUACAGGUGCUGGAAGUGCUGACAGCGGCUGUGGAGUAUGGGCUGGAGGAACUGAGAGAGGUGGGUUUUUGUGCCAGGUCCCUGUCUCAUUUCCCUUGCUUCUCACGGGCUCACUUCCCGCCCUGCCUCACACACACUCUGGCCUGGAGAGGAACGUGUGCCCACACAGAGAGAAGUAUGUAUAUCUCUCCCAACUGUGCCUGCAGUUUGUGGUGAAGGUGCUGGAUGUGGACUUGGUUUGUGAGGCCCUGCAGGUGGCCGUAACCUUUGGCCUGGGGCAGCUGCAGGAGCGCUGCGUGGCUUUCAUAGAGGCCCACAGCCAGGAGGCCCUCCGGACCCGAGGCUUCCUGGAGCUGUCGGCGGCCGCGCUGCUGCCCCUGCUCCGCAGCGACAAGCUCUGCGUGGACGAGGCUGAACUGGUCCGCGCGGCCCGAAGCUGGGCGCGCGUGGGCGCGGCGGUGCUGGAGCGGCCGGUGGCUGAGGUGGCGGCCCCGGUGGUGAAAGAGCUGAGACUAGCCUUGCUGGCCCCGGCGGAGCUGAGCGCCCUGGAAGAGCAGAACCGGCAGGAACCACUCAUCCCGGUGGGGACGCGGGGAACCGGCCCAGCUCCACUCAGCAGGGGGUGGAGCAGAUUGUGGAGGCGUGGAAAUGCCAUGCCCUGCGGAGAGGGGAUGAGGCCCGGGGCGCCCCGUGUCGCCGCCGGAGAGGCACCCUGCCCCGGGAGCAUCACCGCUUUCUGGACCUGUCCUUCAAAUGAUCCAACGCCGGGACUCGCAGGGAGCCCUCGACCCGCCCAGCUGAGCCUGCCCCAAACUACAGCUCCCGAAGUGCUCGGCGUUCGGAGCGGGCUUCCGUUCCCAGCGUGCCCAGUGAGCCGGGCGCCGGAAGAACCGUUGUCUGCCACGCGCAGCCCCUUGUGCGGGAUCAAGCCCGUGUGGGCGAGGUGGGGUCGGGCCGGGCAGGGCUUGGGCUGGGCCUCCCUGAGGGGGUGAAACUCGAAAACGAGGAUUUCCUUCGUUCCACACCCUGACUCUACGCCCUGCCCCUGGGCAUUGUCGUCUACUAGUCUAUUCUGAUGACUCCCACAUAUCUAUCUGUUCAGCUCAGCUCCCUCUUUCUUUUCUUUUUCUUUCUCUUUCUUUCUUUCUUUCUUUCUUUCUUUCUUUCUUUCUUUCUUUCUUUCUUUCUUUCUUUCUUUUUCUUUCUUUCUCUUUCCUUCCUUCCUUCCUUCCUUCCUUCUUUCUUUCUCUUUCUCUAUCUCUUUCUUUCUUUCUUUCUUUCUCUCCUCUCUCUUUUUUUUGAGACGGAGUCUCGCACUCUCGCCCAGGCCGGAGGGCAGUGGUGCCAUCUCGGCUCACUGCAAGCUCCGCCUCCCGGGUUCACGCCGUUCUCCUGCCUCAGCCUCCGGAGUAGCUGGUACUACAGGCGCCCAUCACCACGCCCGGCUAAUUUUUUUGAAUUUUUAGUAGAGACGGAGUUUCACCGUAUUAGCCAGGAUGGUCUCGAUCUCCUGACCUUGUGAUCCGCCCGCCUCGGCCUUUUUUUUUUUUUUUUUGAGACAGAGUCUUGCUCUGUCGUCGAGGCUGGAGUGUAGUGGUGCGAUUUCGGCUCACUUCAAACUCCGCCUCCCGGGUUCAAGCGAUUCUCGUGCCUCAGCCUCCUGAGUAGCUGGGAUUACAGACAUGCACCACAACGCCCGGCUAAUUGUUGUAUUUUUAGUAGAGACGGGGGUUUCACCAUGUUGGCCAGGUUGGUCUCGAACUCCUGACUUCAUGUGAUCCGCCAGCCUCGGCCUCCCAAAGUGCUGGGAUUACAGGUGUGCGCCACCAUGCCCGGCCUCAGCUCCUUCUUUCAUUCCAGACCUGCCCCCCUGGAGAUCGCUCCCUGAAUGCCCCUCAGACACCACAGGCUCGGCGAGAAAUUGAUCUCCCCAGCUUUUCCCCAGCUCUGCCCCCAUCGUGUUUCUCAUUUCCGUGGACACCCACGCCAGAAACCUGGAUCUCAUCCUUGCCUUAUCGCUCUUCACACCUGCCUUAGGUCUCUUUUUACCUUGUAAGAGACCUUAAGAGACCUUUCCAGUUGGUUCAGUUCUCUCAGCCCCAGGUUCAACCUGUCCUGUCUGACACGUCUCACAGCCUUCCUGCCUUCACUCCAGCGCCCCCUCAAUCCAUUUCCCACAGUGCAGCCAGACCUGUUUUUGAUUGUCAGUCCUAUGGGGCUUAAGUCCUGGAACAUCCCAUUGACCUCCAGGACAAAAUUCAAUCUAUUUCACUUUCAGGGCACUCAAAACUACUAGUGAGUGGUUCCUCACCUCUUCUCUCAAAUACAAUCUUUGUAUAAAUUCAUUUAUCCUGGAGGUAUUAGUCCUCUAGCUCCAUACCUUACUCAGUUACUGCAGACCCCUCUGCUACCUCCUUCAUUCACUAUACAUCUUGUUUUCCCGAGGAUGUGAAUCUCCCUCAAGAAAGAUCCCUGGGGCCUGGAGUGGUGUCUUACUCGUUUCUGCUUCCUCAGUCUCUGUCAGAUAAUCAGUGCUAUGUAAAUGUUAAGUAAAUGACUUUAUUUAUUUA